GAGGUACGGCCUCCCGGGGACCUUCCAGACUGGUCGGCGCAAGCGAAGGGCGGGGACCACCGAAGGAGUGUGUGACUUAGGCAUCCAGCGCACUGCCUGACCCGAAGUACCGACCCGAGUUAUGCCCACCCUCCAACUUUGCGACGGAAAUGUGUCAUCGAAAGCCAGGUACACCAGGGGUUGGAAAAACCACACUAGGCAAAGAACUUGCGUCAAAAUCAGGACUGAAAUACAUUAAUGUGGGUGAUUUAGCUCGAGAAGUCUGAUCAUCGGAUAUCAUGGAGUCUGGCAAGACGGCUUCUCCCAAGAGCAUGCCGAAAGAUGCACAGAUGAUGGCACAAAUCCUGAAGGAUAUGGGGAUUACAGAAUAUGAGCCAAGAGUUAUAAAUCAGAUGUUGGAGUUUGCCUUCCGAUAUGUGACCACAAUUCUAGAUGAUGCAAAAAUUUAUUCAAGCCAUGCUAAGAAAGCUACUGUUGAUGCAGAUGAUGUGCGAUUGGCAAUCCAGUGCCGCGCUGAUCAGUCUUUUACCUCUCCUCCCCCAAGAGAUUUUUUAUUAGAUAUUGCAAGGCAAAGAAAUCAAACCCCUUUGCCAUUGAUCAAGCCAUAUUCAGGUCCUAGGUUGCCACCUGAUAGAUACUGCUUAACAGCUCCAAACUAUAGGCUGAAAUCUUUACAGAAAAAGGCAUCAACUUCUGCGGGAAGAAUAACAGUCCCGCGGUUAAGUGUUGGUUCAGUUACUAGCAGACCAAGUACUCCCACACUAGGCACACCAACCCCACAGACCAUGUCUGUUUCAACUAAAGUAGGGACUCCCAUGUCCCUCACAGGUCAAAGGUUUACAGUACAGAUGCCUACUUCUCAGUCUCCAGCUGUAAAAGCUUCAAUUCCUGCAACCUCAGCAGUUCAGAAUGUUCUGAUUAAUCCAUCAUUAAUCGGGUCCAAAAACAUUCUUAUUACCACUAAUAUGAUGUCAUCACAAAAUACUGCCAAUGAAUCAUCAAAUGCAUUGAAAAGAAAACGUGAAGAUGAUGAUGAUGACGAUGAUGAUGAUGAUGACUAUGAUAAUCUGUAAUCUAGCCUUGCUGAAUGUAACAUGUAUACUUGGUCUUGAAUUCAUUGUACUGAUAUUAAACAUGCAUGCUGGAUGUUUUCAAGUUGUGUUUUAGAAAACUAAUAAUAAUGAGUAAACACAGUUACCAUACUUUUCAAUUGAAAUGAAGGUUUUUCAUCAGCCUUAAAAGUGUAAGAAAAAUAAAGUUGUCAUUCAUUCGA